CUUUCCCGCCCCAGCCCUACCCCCUCAUUCUGGUCCCAUCCUCUUCCUCCUGCCCCAAUCCUCAAUGCGCCUCCAUCCUCGCCUGCCUUCUCUCGGUCCCUCGUGAUUGAUUCCACCCUUGCUUCCCCUUUCUCCGCGCCGCCUGUUCCGUGCUCGUUUUCCCCUCUUCCUCCUUAAGUCUGGUCCUUCCACCCCCUCCUCUUCAAGCUGUGCGUGUCCCCUGAUUCUAAUGCUUUCUGUGUAACUCAUUGAAACUGCGUUCUGGUUCCCCUCCCGCGUCCAUUCUCCAUUCAUGCGCGACCGCCCUUCCCGCGCCCCAGUUCCCUCUCGCCGCCCCUCCCCCUGCUUGCUGGUCACGUCCGCUCCCCCGCAUCCCCUUCCUCGCCUGGCGUGUCCGCUCCCUCCCUCCCUCUCUGCUCUGGUCGCGCCCGCCCACUUGCUCCGGUCUCCGAGCGCGGUCCCACCCCCCUUUUCCAUCACCGCCUCCCAGCUCCCAGCAGGCUCGGGCGGUGCUGAGGCCCCGUGUCCGGGGCGGGCGGGCGGAGGGCUGGGCUGGGUGCCCCGCGCGGCGGGCGGGAUGCGGCGGCCCGGGGGCAGCUGGAGACUUACGUAACGUUGGCCUGCCCCGCUGCCGGGAGGCAGGGCGGUUGCCCCUGCGGCGCGGUGCCGUCCCCUGUGGCCGGGAUUAGAUGGGCGGCCUGCGAGGGCCUGGGAAUGGCUCGGGGCCCGAGAGCUCGACCGGCCCUUGCCGGGUGGCCGCCAGGGACCACGCUCCAUCUCGCCGCGGCCGGGCUGCACGUAGCGGCCGCGCCCAGGGCCCACCCCGCUUCACCGGGCGAUGGCCUUGGGCCUCGUAACGGGCGGGAUAAACCUCUGCAGGCUUUGCUGGGGCCUCCUGGCCCUCGCCCGUUCCGCGCCUCUCCGGCACGUUUCUUUCUUUUCCUUUCUUUUUUCUUUCUUUUUUUUUUUUUUAAUUAUCCGGCACAUUUUUUAACAAAUGCGUCCUGAUUGUGGAACGCGGAGGCCGCGGGGUGGGGUGGGGAUCUGGUUACGGAGGGGGCAGGAAAUCUGUCGCGUUCACUGAACGCAAACGGUGUGGGUCAAGGGCUGUUUGGGGGUCAGAGUUAGAGACCAGGAUGACUAGACGAGUCAUAGCCCACCGAGCUCACAAUCUUAAAAUGUAUCUCCUGUAAUGCUGGGAGUGGGGUACGAGCUUCCUGCUGUGGGAGGGAGGGGGACAGGAAGCCUCGUAAGGUCUCACCAGGUGGCAAGCACACUGGAUUAGAAGAUGCAGGAAAGCACCUUCCAGUCUGAAGAUCAUUUAAAGACUCAGUCAUGUAAGGGCAUCCCUUGGCUUCUUAAUCUACGUACUCCAGACCCAGGGCUUGGACCUUUGCUGGUACGGGUUAAAGUGAGGCCGACAGUGAAGGUCCACGUGGAGAGAGACAUUGGGAAGUUGUCAAAAAGGCGUUUAGAAUCAGGUUUGACUCAUUAAUUUCCUGAGACUCUGAAGGAGUUCAGCCUCUACACCUCAGUUUCCCCUGGGAAAACUGGGAGUAACAUUUUCCUCAUGAUGGUUGAAAGGAUUCAUGCUUACGUGGAUGUGGCACACUCAGUAAGUGUCUAAUCUCUGGCGAAAUACCCAGAAGAAAAGCCUGUGACUGAAUAUAUUAUUUUUGAGCACAAUUACUUAGUCCACAAUUGAGCAUAAGGGCCUUGAUCCAUUGUCUUCCUACUGUCCCCAAACGCCUACAGCUAAUCGUGAGGAAUCAGGCUCUCUGAAUAACCACGUGUCUCCUGGAAACCAGUUCCCCAAGGGAUCUGGUUUAAUAUUGACAAAGUAACUGAUAAUGUAACUUUCCAACUCUCUGCUUGGAGCAGAUGCUUUUUGGUCAUCUGAGAUUGGGACCUGUAGACAAAGGCAGGCAAGGAGGGGCUGAGUUAAGCCUUUGGUGUUCCGCUGUAAGUAGAAUACUACCUACCAGAGGAACAUUCCAGCCCUUGACUUGCUCUGCCUGCUGGUGAGAUUAGGAUUGGAGCCAGGGUCAGUAGCCCCCAGUUGGCCGUCUUGAGGGUGUGGCCACUCCCUAGGUCACAGAGGAGAUGGAGGUCAGGACUCCCCUGCUGCAGCGUUGUUAGCAAAUAAUUUGCCCUUUGGUGGCCUGAGGUGCUGUGGGGGCAGGAGUGGGCUGUCUUGUGGGGAAGGGAAAUGUAACGUAUCACCAAAUCUGUGGGGGAGUGGGGCUCUGUGGGGAAGAUGACUCAACCUUUCAAUUAUUCUGCUUUUGAGAGAAUUAUCUUCGCUGGCUCUCCAGGGCACACCGUAUUCAGCUCUGAGCGGUCUUUGCUAGUGAGGCCAAGGAGCCACCCUGAGCCAAAAGGGGAGCAUUAUGUCACCGGAAGCCCAACCCCAGAGAACCAAAGGACCUCAGCAGCCAUGUCGAAGCCCCAUAGUGAAGCCGGGACUGCCUUCAUUCAGACCCAGCAGCUGCACGCAGCCAUGGCUGACACAUUCCUGGAGCACAUGUGCCGCCUGGACAUUGAUUCACCACCCAUCACAGCCCGGAACACUGGCAUCAUCUGUACCAUUGGCCCAGCUUCCCGAUCAGUGGAGACGUUGAAGGAGAUGAUUAAGUCUGGAAUGAAUGUGGCUCGUCUGAACUUCUCUCAUGGAACUCAUGAGUACCAUGCGGAGACCAUCAAGAAUGUGCGCACAGCCACGGAAAGCUUUGCUUCUGACCCCAUCCUCUACCGGCCCGUUGCUGUGGCUCUAGACACUAAAGGACCUGAGAUCCGAACUGGGCUCAUCAAGGGCAGCGGCACUGCAGAGGUGGAGCUGAAGAAGGGAGCCACUCUCAAAAUCACGCUGGAUAACGCCUACAUGGAAAAGUGUGACGAGAACAUCCUGUGGCUGGACUACAAGAACAUCUGCAAGGUGGUGGAAGUGGGCAGCAAGAUCUACGUGGAUGAUGGGCUUAUUUCUCUCCAGGUGAAGCAGAAAGGUGCCGACUUCCUGGUGACGGAGGUGGAAAAUGGUGGCUCCUUGGGCAGCAAGAAGGGUGUGAACCUUCCUGGGGCUGCUGUGGACUUGCCUGCUGUGUCGGAGAAGGACAUCCAGGAUCUGAAGUUUGGGGUCGAGCAGGAUGUUGAUAUGGUGUUUGCGUCAUUCAUCCGCAAGGCAUCUGAUGUCCAUGAAGUUAGGAAGGUCCUGGGAGAGAAGGGAAAGAACAUCAAGAUUAUCAGCAAAAUCGAGAAUCAUGAGGGGGUUCGGAGGUUUGAUGAAAUCCUGGAGGCCAGUGAUGGGAUCAUGGUGGCUCGUGGUGAUCUAGGCAUUGAGAUUCCUGCAGAGAAGGUCUUCCUUGCUCAGAAGAUGAUGAUUGGACGGUGCAACCGAGCUGGGAAGCCUGUCAUCUGUGCUACUCAGAUGCUGGAGAGCAUGAUCAAGAAGCCCCGCCCCACUCGGGCUGAAGGCAGUGAUGUGGCCAAUGCAGUCCUGGAUGGAGCCGACUGCAUCAUGCUGUCUGGAGAAACAGCCAAAGGGGACUAUCCUCUGGAGGCUGUGCGCAUGCAGCACCUGAUUGCCCGUGAGGCAGAGGCUGCCAUCUACCACUUGCAAUUAUUUGAGGAACUCCGCCGCCUGGCGCCCAUUACCAGCGACCCCACAGAAGCCACCGCCGUGGGUGCCGUGGAGGCCUCCUUCAAGUGCUGCAGUGGGGCCAUAAUCGUCCUCACCAAGUCUGGCAGGUCUGCUCACCAGGUGGCCAGAUACCGCCCACGUGCCCCCAUCAUUGCUGUGACCCGGAAUCCCCAGACAGCUCGUCAGGCCCACCUGUACCGUGGCAUCUUCCCUGUGCUGUGCAAGGACCCAGUCCAGGAGGCCUGGGCUGAGGACGUGGACCUCCGGGUGAACUUUGCCAUGAAUGUUGGCAAGGCCCGAGGCUUCUUCAAGAAGGGAGAUGUGGUCAUUGUGCUGACCGGAUGGCGCCCUGGCUCCGGCUUCACCAACACCAUGCGUGUUGUUCCUGUGCCGUGAUGGACCCCAGAGCCCCUCCUCCAGCCCCUGUCCCACCCCCUUCCCCCAGCCCAUCCAUUAGGCCAGCAACGCUUGUAGAACUCACUCUGGGCUGUAACGUGGCACUGGUAGGUUGGGACACCAGGGAAGAAGAUCAACGCCUCACUGAAACAUGGCUGUGUUUGCAGCCUGCUCUAGUGGGACAGCCCAGAGCCUGGCUGCCCAUCAUGUGGCCCCACCCAAUCAAGGGAAGAAGGAGGAAUGCUGGACUGGAGGCCCCUGGAGCCAGAUGGCAAGAGGGUGACAGCUUCCUUUCCUGUGUGUACUCUGUCCAGUUCCUUUAGAAAAAAUGGAUGCCCAGAGGACUCCCAACCCUGGCUUGGGGUCAAGAAACAGCCAGCAAGAGUUAGGGGCCUUAGGGCACUGGGCUGUUGUUCCAUUGAAGCCGACUCUGGCCCUGGCCCUUACUUGCUUCUCUAGCUCUCUAGGCCUCUCCAGUUUGCACCUGUCCCCACCCUCCACUCAGCUGUCCUGCAGCAAACACUCCACCCUCCACCUUCCAUUUUCCCCCACUACUGCAGCACCUCCAGGCCUGUUGCUAUAGAGCCUACCUGUAUGUCAAUAAACAACAGCUGAAGCACC